GUCACUCGGGCCCCGCCGGUGGCCCGGGGAAGCAGCACGGGCGGGGGGCAGGGGCUGGGGCCGACCGGGAGGCCGGUGCCAAGGAUGGGGGCCGCCCGGCUGCCCCGCGCGUGAGGAGGCCGAGGGGCGCGCCACCCCGGCCCGGGGCGGCCGCCCCAGGGGCCCCGCCACCCCCGCCCGGCCCGGCAGUCGUGGCCCGGGAUGCGGAGCCGGGGGCCGCCGGUGGAGCUGCGCGGGGUGAGCGGCGCGGGGAACGGGGACUGCCUGCCGCCCUCGCCCUCGUCCCCCACCGGCGGACCCCGGCGGGCAUUCGAGAGCCGCGCGGCCAGGCCCUCUUAGCCCUCUGCCGUUUGGGGGGCACGGGUGAACCUGCCGCCCCACUCCCACCCCGCCCCGCCCCGCCCGUACAGCCAAAUCGGAAGGGACGAGCCUGCCCUUUGAAAGGGUUUUUUUUCUUGCUCCUGCGGAGGGCGCCCCAGCCAUGGCCCUCAGGAGCUCCCUAGACCCCGCAGGGACUGCCCUCCAUCCCGGCCGCCGGGGCCCGCCCUCUGCAUCCCGCGGGCAGCCUGUGUGAAGCGGCCUCCCGCAGCCCCCGGCCCCUCCCCCAUGGAGGAGGAGGAGGGGGCGGUGGCCAAGGAGUGGGGCACGACCCCCGCGGGGCCCGUCUGGACCGCGGUGUUCGACUACGAGGCGGCGGGCGACGAGGAGCUGACCCUGCGGAGGGGCGAUCGCGUCCAGGUGCUUUCCCAAGACUGUGCGGUGUCCGGCGACGAGGGCUGGUGGACCGGGCAGCUCCCCAGCGGCCGCGUGGGCGUCUUCCCCAGCAACUACGUGGCCCCCGGCGCCCCCGCUGCACCCGCGGGCCUCCAGCUGCCCCAGGAGAUCCCCUUCCACGAGCUGCAGCUAGAGGAGAUCAUCGGUGUGGGGGGCUUUGGCAAGGUCUAUCGGGCCCUGUGGCGUGGCGAGGAGGUGGCAGUCAAGGCCGCCCGGCUGGACCCUGAGAAGGACCCGGCAGUGACAGCGGAGCAGGUGUGCCAGGAAGCCCGGCUCUUUGGAGCCCUGCAGCACCCCAACAUAAUUGCCCUUAGGGGCGCCUGCCUCAACCCCCCACACCUCUGCCUAGUGAUGGAGUAUGCCCGGGGUGGUGCACUGAGCAGGGUGCUGGCAGGUCGCCGGGUGCCACCUCACGUGCUGGUCAACUGGGCUGUGCAGGUGGCCCGGGGCAUGAACUACCUACACAAUGAUGCCCCUGUGCCCAUCAUCCACCGGGACCUCAAGUCCAUCAACAUCCUGAUCCUGGAGGCCAUCGAGAACCACAACCUCGCAGACACGGUGCUCAAGAUCACGGACUUCGGCCUCGCCCGCGAGUGGCACAAGACCACCAAGAUGAGCGCUGCGGGGACCUACGCCUGGAUGGCGCCGGAGGUUAUCCGUCUCUCCCUCUUCUCCAAAAGCAGUGAUGUCUGGAGCUUCGGGGUGCUGCUGUGGGAGCUGCUGACGGGGGAGGUCCCCUACCGUGAGAUCGACGCCUUGGCCGUGGCGUAUGGCGUGGCUAUGAAUAAGCUGACGCUGCCCAUUCCCUCCACGUGCCCCGAGCCCUUUGCCCGCCUCCUGGAGGGUGAGCCGGGGCCCCGUGACGAGGAAUGCUGGGACCCAGACCCCCACGGGCGGCCAGAUUUCGGUAGCAUCUUGAAGCGGCUUGAAGUCAUCGAACAGUCAGCCCUGUUCCAGAUGCCACUGGAGUCCUUCCACUCGCUGCAGGAAGACUGGAAGCUGGAGAUUCAGCACAUGUUUGAUGACCUUCGGACCAAGGAGAAGGAGCUUCGGAGCCGUGAGGAGGAGCUGCUGCGGGCGGCACAGGAGCAGCGCUUCCAGGAGGAGCAGCUGCGGCGGCGGGAGCAGGAGCUGGCAGAACGUGAGAUGGACAUCGUGGAACGGGAGCUGCACCUGCUCAUGUGCCAGCUGAGCCAGGAGAAGCCCCGGGUCCGCAAGCGCAAGGGCAACUUCAAGCGCAGCCGCCUGCUCAAGCUGCGGGAAGGCGGCAGCCACAUCAGCCUGCCCUCUGGCUUUGAGCAUAAGAUCACAGUCCAGGCCUCUCCAACUCUGGAUAAGCGGAAAGGAUCCGAUGGGGCCAGCCCCCCUGCAAGCCCCAGCAUCAUCCCCCGGCUGAGGGCCAUUCGCCUGACUCCCGUGGACUGUGGUGGCAGCAGCAGUGGCAGCAGCAGUGGAGGAAGUGGGACAUGGAGCCGCGGUGGGCCCCCAAAGAAGGAAGAACUGGUCGGGGGCAAGAAGAAGGGACGAACGUGGGGGCCCAGCUCCACCCUGCAGAAGGAGCGGGUGGGAGGAGAGGAGAGGCUGAAGGGGCUGGGGGAAGGAAGCAAACAGUGGUCAUCAAGUGCCCCCAACCUGGGCAAGUCCCCCAAACACACACCCAUCGCCCCUGGCUUUGCCAGCCUCAAUGAGAUGGAGGAGUUCGCGGAGGCAGAGGAUGGAGGCAGCAGCGUGCCCCCUUCCCCCUACUCGACCCCGUCCUACCUCUCAGUGCCACUGCCUGCCGAGCCCUCCCCGGGGGCGCGGGCGCCGUGGGAGCCGACGCCGUCCGCGCCCCCCGCUCGGUGGGGACACGGCGCCCGGCGGCGCUGCGACCUGGCGCUGCUAGGCUGCGCCACGCUGCUGGGGGCUGUGGGCCUGGGCGCCGACGUGGCCGAGGCGCGCGCGGCCGACGGUGAGGAGCAGCGGCGCUGGCUCGACGGCCUCUUCUUUCCCCGCGCCGGCCGCUUCCCGCGGGGCCUCAGCCCACCCGCGCGUCCCCACGGCCGCCGCGAAGACGUGGGCCCCGGCCUGGGCCUGGCGCCCUCGGCCACCCUCGUGUCGCUGUCGUCCGUGUCCGACUGCAACUCCACGCGUUCACUGCUGCGCUCUGACAGUGACGAGGCCGCACCGGCCGCGCCCUCCCCACCACCCUCCCCGCCCGCGCCCACACCCACGCCCUCGCCCAGCACCAACCCCCUGGUGGACCUGGAGCUGGAGAGCUUCAAGAAGGACCCCCGCCAGUCGCUCACGCCCACCCACGUCACGGCUGCAUGCGCUGUGAGCCGCGGGCACCGGCGGACGCCAUCGGACGGGGCGCUGGGGCAGCGGGGGCCGCCCGAGCCCGCGGGCCAUGGCCCUGGCCCUCGUGACCUUCUGGACUUCCCCCGCCUGCCCGACCCCCAGGCCCUGUUCCCAGCCCGCCGCCGGCCCCCUGAGUUCCCAGGCCGCCCCACCACCCUGACCUUUGCCCCGAGACCUCGGCCGGCUGCCAGUCGCCCCCGCUUGGACCCCUGGAAACUGGUCUCCUUCGGCCGGACACUCACCAUCUCGCCUCCCAGCAGGCCAGACACUCCGGAGAGCCCUGGGCCCCCCAGCGUGCAGCCCACACUGCUGGACAUGGACAUGGAGGGGCAGAACCAAGACAGCACAGUGCCCCUGUGCGGGGCCCACGGCUCCCACUAAGGCCUGCCCACCACCGCCCGCCUGGGCAGCCAUGAAUGUAGCGCCCCAGGCCCUGCCCCAGCCCGCCAUGCCACAAGGUGGGGGAGGCCCUGGGCAGGAUGUUCACUCUAUUUAUUGGGGAAGGAGGGAGGGGGGGGACACUUAACUUAUUCCUUUGUACCCCAGGGGGUGGAGCCCUGUGCCCACCCUGCACUGGGGGGAGGGUGGGCAGGGAUACUCAGGGACAGGGCAUCAUGGGGGAUUUGGCACAAAAUGGAGCAUUAAAGGUAACCCCUGCCCCCUA